GCAAAGCUGCAGCGUCUGGAAAAAAGCGACUUGUGGCGGUCGAGCGUGGCGCAGGCGAAUCCUCGGCACUAAGCAAAUAUGGACCUCGCGGCGGCAGCGGAGCCGGGCGCCGGCAGCCAGCACCUGGAGGUCCGCGACGAGGUGGCCGAGAAGUGCCAGAAACUGUUCCUGGACUUCUUGGAGGAGUUUCAGAGCAGCGAUGGAGAAAUUAAAUACUUGCAAUUAGCAGAGGAACUGAUUCGUCCUGAGAGAAACACAUUGGUUGUGAGUUUUGUGGACCUGGAACAAUUUAACCAGCAACUUUCCACCACCAUUCAAGAGGAGUUCUAUAGAGUUUACCCUUACCUGUGUCGGGCCUUGAAAACAUUCGUCAAAGACCGUAAAGAGAUCCCUCUUGCCAAGGAUUUUUAUGUUGCAUUCCAAGACCUGCCUACCAGACACAAGAUUCGAGAGCUCACCUCAUCCAGAAUUGGUUUGCUCACUCGCAUCAGUGGGCAGGUGGUGCGGACUCACCCAGUUCACCCAGAGCUUGUGAGCGGAACUUUUCUGUGCUUGGACUGUCAGACAGUGAUCAGGGAUGUAGAACAGCAGUUCAAAUACACACAGCCAAACAUCUGCCGAAAUCCAGUUUGUGCCAACAGGAGGAGAUUCUUACUGGAUACAAAUAAAUCAAGAUUUGUUGAUUUUCAAAAGGUUCGUAUUCAAGAGACCCAAGCUGAGCUUCCUCGAGGGAGUAUCCCCCGCAGUUUAGAAGUAAUUUUAAGGGCUGAAGCUGUGGAAUCAGCUCAAGCUGGUGACAAGUGUGACUUUACAGGGACACUGAUUGUUGUGCCUGACGUCUCCAAGCUUAGCACACCAGGAGCACGUGCAGAAACUAAUUCCCGUGUCAGUGGUGUUGAUGGAUAUGAGACAGAAGGCAUUCGAGGACUCCGGGCCCUUGGUGUUAGGGACCUUUCUUAUAGGCUGGUCUUUCUUGCCUGCUGUGUUGCGCCAACCAACCCAAGGUUUGGGGGGAAAGAGCUCAGAGAUGAGGAACAGACAGCUGAGAGCAUUAAGAACCAAAUGACUGUGAAAGAAUGGGAGAAAGUGUUUGAGAUGAGUCAAGAUAAAAAUCUAUACCACAAUCUUUGUACCAGCCUGUUCCCUACUAUACAUGGCAAUGAUGAAGUAAAACGGGGUGUCCUGCUGAUGCUCUUUGGUGGCGUUCCAAAGACAACAGGAGAAGGGACCUCUCUUCGAGGGGACAUAAAUGUUUGCAUUGUUGGUGACCCAAGUACAGCUAAGAGCCAAUUUCUCAAGCACGUGGAGGAGUUCAGCCCCAGAGCUGUCUACACCAGUGGUAAAGCGUCCAGUGCUGCUGGCUUAACAGCAGCUGUUGUGAGAGAUGAAGAAUCUCAUGAGUUUGUCAUUGAGGCUGGAGCUUUGAUGUUGGCUGAUAAUGGUGUGUGUUGUAUUGAUGAAUUUGAUAAGAUGGACGUGCGGGAUCAAGUUGCUAUUCAUGAAGCUAUGGAACAGCAGACCAUAUCCAUCACUAAAGCAGGAGUGAAGGCUACUCUGAACGCCCGGACGUCCAUUUUGGCAGCAGCAAACCCAAUCAGUGGACACUAUGACAGAUCAAAAUCAUUGAAACAGAAUAUAAAUUUGUCAGCUCCCAUCAUGUCCCGAUUCGAUCUCUUCUUUAUCCUUGUGGAUGAAUGUAAUGAGGUUACAGAUUAUGCCAUUGCCAGGCGCAUAGUAGAUUUGCAUUCAAGAAUUGAGGAAUCAAUUGAUCGUGUCUAUUCCCUCGAUGAUAUCAGAAGAUAUCUUCUCUUUGCAAGACAGUUUAAACCCAAGAUUUCCAAAGAGUCAGAGGACUUCAUUGUGGAGCAAUAUAAACAUCUCCGCCAGAGAGAUGGUUCUGGAGUGACCAAGUCUUCAUGGAGGAUUACAGUGCGACAGCUUGAGAGCAUGAUUCGUCUCUCUGAAGCUAUGGCUCGGAUGCACUGCUGUGAUGAGGUCCAACCUAAACAUGUGAAGGAAGCUUUCCGGUUACUGAAUAAAUCAAUCAUCCGUGUGGAAACACCUGAUGUCAAUCUAGAUCAAGAGGAAGAGAUCCAGAUGGAGGUAGAUGAGGGUGCUGGUGGCAUCAAUGGUCAUGCUGACAGCCCUGCUCCUGUGAACGGGAUCAAUGGCUACAAUGAAGACAUAAAUCAAGAGUCUGCUCCCAAAGCCUCCUUAAGGCUGGGCUUCUCUGAGUACUGCCGAAUCUCUAACCUUAUUGUGCUUCACCUCAGAAAGGUGGAAGAAGAAGAGGACGAGUCAGCAUUAAAGAGGAGCGAGCUUGUUAACUGGUACUUGAAGGAAAUCGAAUCAGAGAUAGACUCUGAAGAAGAACUUAUAAAUAAAAAAAGAAUCAUAGAGAAAGUUAUUCAUCGACUCACACACUAUGAUCAUGUUCUAAUUGAGCUCACCCAGGCUGGAUUGAAAGGCUCCACAGAGGGAAGUGAGAGCUAUGAAGAAGAUCCCUACUUGGUAGUUAACCCUAACUACUUGCUCGAAGAUUGAGAUAGUGAAAGUAACUGACCAGAGCUGAGGAACUGUGGCACAGCACCUCGUGGCCUGGAGCCUGGCUGGAGCUCUGCUAGGGACAGAAGUGUUUCUGGAAGUGAUGCUUCCAGGAUUUGUUUUCAGAAACAAGAAUUGAGUUGAUGGUCCUAUGUGUCACAUUCAUCACAGGUUUCAUACCAACACAGGCUUCAGCACUUCCUUUGGUGUGUUUCCUGUCCCAGUGAAGUUGGAACCAAAUAAUGUGUAGUCUCUAUAACCAAUACCUUUGUUUUCAUGUGUAAGAAAAGGCCCAUUACUUUUAAGGUAUGUGCUGUCCUAUUGAGCAAAUAACUUUUUUUCAAUUGCCAGCUACUGCUUUUAUUCAUCAAAAUAAAAUAACUUGUUCUGAAGUUGUCUAUUGGAUUUCUUUCUACUGUACCCUGAUUAUUACUUCCAUCUACUUCUGAAUGUGAGACUUUCCCUUUUUGCUUAACCUGGAGUGAAGAGGUAGAACUGUGGUAUUAUGGAUGAGGUUUCUAUGAGAAGGAGUCAUUAGAGAACUCAUAUGAAAGCUAGAGGCCUUAGAGAUGACUUUCCAAGGUUAAUUCCAGUUGUUUUUUUUUUUUUUUAAGUUUAUAAAAGUUUAUUAUACUUUUUUAAAAUUACUCUUUAGUAAUUUAUUUUACUUCUGUGUCCUAAGGGUAAUUUCUCAGGAUUGUUUUCAAAUUGCUUUUUUAGGGGAAAUAGGUCAUUUGCUAUAUUACAAGCAAUCCCCAAAUUUUAUGGUCUUCCAGGAAAAGUUAUUACCGUUUAUGAUACUAACAGUUCCUGAGACUUAGCUAUGAUCAGUAUGUUCAUGAGGUGGAGCAGUUCCUGUGUUGCAGCUUUUAACAACAGAUGGCAUUCAUUAAAUCACAAAGUAUGUUAAAGGUCACAAAAGCAAAAUAACUGUCUGAGGCUAAGGCCCACGUGGGACAGUCUAAUACCCAUGAGUACUCAACUUGCCUUGAUGUCUGAGCUUUCCAGUGCAAUGUGAAUUUGAGCAGCCAGAAAUCUAUUAGUAGAAAGCAAGACAGAUUAAUAUAGGUUAAAACAAUGAUUUAAAUAUGUUUCUCCCAAUAAUUAUCUCUUUCCCUGGAAUCAACUUGUAUGAAACCUUGUCAAAAUGUACUCCACAAGUAUGUACAAUUAAGUAUUUUAAAAAUAAAUGGCAAACAUUAAAAACAA